AUUGUUGCAAGAUGGCCGCGCCCAGUGAUGGAUUCAAGCCUCGUGAACGAAGCGGUGGGGAGCAGGCACAGGACUGGGAUGCUCUGCCACCCAAGCGGCCCCGACUAGGGGCAGGAAACAAGAUCGGAGGCCGUAGGCUUAUUGUGGUGCUGGAAGGGGCCAGUCUGGAGACAGUCAAGGUAGGGAAGACAUAUGAGCUACUCAACUGUGACAAGCACAAGUCUAUAUUGUUGAAGAAUGGACGGGACCCUGGGGAAGCGCGGCCAGAUAUCACCCACCAGAGUUUGCUGAUGCUGAUGGAUAGUCCCCUGAACCGAGCUGGCUUGCUACAGGUUUAUAUCCAUACACAGAAGAAUGUUCUGAUUGAAGUGAAUCCCCAGACCCGAAUUCCCAGAACCUUUGACCGCUUUUGUGGCCUCAUGGUUCAACUUUUACACAAGCUCAGUGUUCGAGCAGCUGAUGGCCCCCAGAAGCUUUUGAAGGUAAUUAAGAAUCCAGUAUCAGAUCACUUUCCAGUUGGAUGUAUGAAAGUUGGCACUUCUUUUUCCAUCCCGGUUGUCAGUGAUGUGCGUGAGCUGGUGCCCAGCAGUGAUCCUAUUGUUUUUGUGGUAGGGGCCUUUGCCCAUGGCAAGGUCAGUGUGGAGUAUACAGAGAAGAUGGUGUCCAUCAGUAACUACCCCCUUUCUGCUGCCCUCACCUGUGCAAAACUUACCACAGCCUUUGAGGAAGUAUGGGGGGUCAUUUGACAGUAGUAGAACCUGUUCUGAAACCAGAAACUGUUGAUGUCACAUCCUUUGACCCUGGUCUGAGCUGACUGCUGGAAGAUGAUCUUUCUGCACUGAGACUGUGGAGUUUGGGGAAGCCAAGGCUGUACAUUUGCUAUUUGUUUAUCCUAUGAAUACUGUUCUUGCAAACCUGGUUGUUUUGGGGUUCCUAAAGUAUCCAGUGGUGUAAAACUGUUUGUUCCCCGGGACUUCAGGGACAGAUAGGAGGUUACAGAGUUUGCAGUUUGGUUCCAUGCUUUGAAGGCAGGCUUUAGCUCCCAGAUUCCCAUGUGCUAAAGGAGAGAACCCUGAUGAUGGAGAAGAACUGUGAAAGAGAGCAGUCAGGAAUGCUAGUGGUGAAAAACUGAACAAACAGAAGUGAUUUUAUCUAAUACAGUUCCAAGGUAGAAAAAGUGGAGCAGGCAGGGCCUUGCACCCCUCUCCACCCCCCCAUGGGGGGGGUGGUGGUAGCGGCACAUACACAAUCAUAGUAAAUUGGCAGAAGAAAAACACAAUAGAUUCCUGGCUAGAUGGGGAGAGAUAAGGCAAUGUGCAUGGGGGAAUCAGAGGGGAGAUGUGAGCCCCUCUGCUCCUCCCACAAGAGUUUCCCCUUUGGGCCGGGCACGGUGGCUCACGCCUGUAAUCCCAGCACUUUGGGAGGCGGAGGCGGGUGGAUCACUUGCGGUCAGGAGUUCGAGACCAGCCUGGCCAACGUGGUGAAAUCCCGUUUCUACUGAAAAUACAAAAAUUAGCUGGGCAUGGUGGCGUGCCUGUAUUCCCAGCUACUUGGGAGGCUGAGGCAGGAAAAUCACUUGAACCCAGGAGGUGGAGGUUGCGGUGAGCUGAGAUCCCGCCACUGCAUUCCAGCGUGGGUGACAAAGCAAGACGCCUUCUCCAAAAAAAAGUUUCCCCUUUGGCCCCAAAUGAAGACUUGGCUGGCAGCAGAGGCACAGCUGGAAGCAUCGAUCUUCCACCUCCCUGGCUUUUCCAUUCUCUGCUCUGGGGCAAAGGAGUGCUGUGAAAAGGGAGACGAGUAGUUUCUGCACCAGUCCCGCACAGGCCACCUGCAAGACAAGAGGAGUUUGGAAGGCUGGUUAGUUACUCCUGUAAUUCCUGGUCUAUAGCCCUUCCAGAUGUUUCCUAGCAUGCCUCAAUAAGUCACAGUAGUCAUUGCCCAUACUGUGUUCCUUAGUAGCCAGGCUAAUCCUUGGAAUUCACCCCAGAUUUCUAAUACUAUUGUUUUUUUCCAGUCUGUUGCUCUAUUCUGUAACCUGGUGGUAGUUUUAGUUUAGCUGUAUUAACUUACCAGGGAAAUGGAUUAUUCCAUCUUCUUUAACUUCUCUUUCCUUGGCACCAUUGCUUUGUGAAUAUAAGGCAAUAUGAAUAGUAGGCUCAGGAAGAAGAUGUGGCCAAGGAAAUAGAUGGAUUUAUACACCUGUGGAGAGAGAGGCCACUAAGGUAGACAGGCCUGGAGUGUCCUUUGCAACCUUUGAGGUUGCAGUGAGUCCCUCCCAGUCUCACAAGCAGGCCUUCACUUGCCUUAAGCCAUUUGUCCCACGUGAAGAGGCAGAAGGCAGUCAUGGAGUAACCCAUGAAGAGCCAGUGGAUGGUCUGUUGCACCAAAUAGUAGAAGGGCUGGAGGACAGUAAUGGCGGCCAGCUUGCUCAGGGUGGGGCUCUCUUGAAUGAGCCUGGCAGCCUGGGGAGGGAGGAGGAGCUCAUCAGCAUCUUGUCCCUUAUAUUCCCCUUCACCCCCACCCUGGAGGCCUACCUGUCUUUCCACAAUAACAAUGAGGAAUUCCAUCUGGAAGCAGACCAGGUAUCCUGAGUGCAGGCCGUGCCAGAGGGCCAGGAAUAGCAACGAGAGACCCUGAGAGAGUUCUUUAUUUCCAAGGAACUUGAGUCGUUUGAAGAUGUAGCUGGAGAAAAGGGUGGGUGGGGCGACCCUCAAACUGACUGGUCCUUGCAUCCCGCCACCUGCCUCUGGGUCCUCACCCUGAGGAUUGGAUUGGAGUGCUGGUGGGUUCCCACGUGUAGCCCCCAGAGGGUACAGGAGGCAGUGCUGACUGAUUACUUUUAGAGAUGGAAAGCAGACCCAAGGCGGAGCUGGAGACCGUGUGCGCACGAGCCACUUGGUUCAGCAGCAGUGACUGAGGCUGAUGCUGAGAUCAGUGGUGAACCAGACACUCUACUCAAGCUGCCCACACUCUAGUGGUGGGGACAAACAAGUAAAGCUGUUGAUAAACAGGGCAGUGGAGGACAUAAGUCCAUUGGCAGAGCUGGAGUAACACCCAGGUCUUAACGCACUUUUAUAUCUUGCCUUUUUUUCAAAUAUGACAGUAAUGGUUUUUUUGGGAGGGGGGUAUAGGUGGGGGUCAAAGUCAGUGUGAGCGACAGGGGGUUCUGCCCAGAUGGGAAAGACGCAUAGGGGUGACAUGGUACACCCCUGCCCUCCAAUCUGGGAAGACAGUGGAAGGAAGGAACCAGGGUCCAGGCUCCCCACCAGCAGCUCACCGGGCCACCCAGGCGUUGGUGUUGAUGUUGAAUGAGGCAAUGGUGCCAGUGAAGCGGGGGUUUGUUUCAAAGAGCCACACCUUCAUGUUGGCACAGGCAUCCCACUUUGCCUUGCCCUUUUCUUCAAAGCCAUUGAAGCCCAGGCCCGUCAAAAUGCAUACUCCUUCCUGAGAGGGAAUAGCUCAGUUAGGGCUCUUGCCACUCCCCAUACUGGCCCCCAUGGCUUGUCUAAAUAGGACCUUGUUUCAACUUUUCUACUUACUGUGACCAGCCAACAGGUGACAUAUUUGUACAGCACAAACUUGCCCCAGAUCAGCAUGUACAUGCAGCGGAACCAGAAGGGGUGGUUCUUGAGGGAAGAAAGCACAGUGCAUUAGGGAUAUCACAUGACUAGGCAGUUUCUCUCAGCACUCUUCCUUUUCACACUUGUGGCUGGCUACUUCAUACCUGCCUGAGUCCUGCUGCCAGAUGCCCUCAAUAGUCUGGCCUGAUUGCCUUCACAAUAGGCAGAGAGGAAUAAGCAGAGGGCCUGGAGAAUAUUCAUUCGCCUUUCCCUUGGAGAGCCUCAAGGGCAGCACUGUAUUUAACUUCUCUACUGUUUGCCUUCGUUGGCAAAGUGUUUGGAAUGAGCAUUUGGAAUGUUAAGUACAGAGGGGCCCAUAUUGGAUUUUAAUUUAAGGAGAGAAACCUGCCCAGAAUUACUGAACUGUUUUCAAGCCUUUCAGCUGGGCAGGAGCAAAAGCCAGCACUUCCCCCCUUCCCUUGGUUUCUGAAUUCCCUAGAAGUGCCCAAAUGUAUCAGUCAAGAGAAGAAAAUAGGAUGGAGAAUCAGAAGCUGCUGUGCUCUGAGGGGUCACGUGGAUGUGAUAAGGCAAGCUAGGAGCGGCUCCUAGAGAAGGCAACGGGUGCUAAAUGUGCACCUGGCACAGCCCUGUGCCCGCGAAGGUUGUUCAGUGCUGGCUGAUGAACAUGUCCCAGCACGGCUGGCAUUGACAACUCACAGAUCUAGAGCAAAACCAACAUGCACUUGUAGAUGAUAUUUCCUACUUCUCUGCUAUCUGUAGGGAUCCUUGCCUGUCCAUUUUCUAGCUCUGGUGCAGUCAUGCUGCUGCUGCUUUAGUAGACACUCACGUCAUAGUCUUCAGUGAGGAGAUAGUCUUCUGUGAUGUGGGGGCUGAGCAGUGUGUAGCCCACUAGGUAGAAAAGGCCCAGACUCAGGCGCUUGAGAGCAGGAAUGAUGCUGGAAAGGAACGAGUGAAGUUCCUGGUCACAGAGAGCAGAGACUAUUCCCUUCACCCUCUGACCUUCAGUUAUGGAGAGGAGUGUUUAGGGGUGUGGUUGUCUACCUGGAAUGGGAUGAGAAGCUCUGCUGCCCAAAGUGUUUCCUGUUUCAGGGAAAGAUUUCUAUGGCUGGCUAUGAGGAAUGGGGACUGCAAACCUCUUAAGAGUUGUAGGAAAGUCAGGGCAGCAGACAGUGGACCAGUCUUGUGUUUACCCCUCAGGGAUGCUACUGAUCUCAAGGUCUUGCCAGGUCUCACAAUCUCCAUUGGGACUGAAAACCCAGUGGAGGUAAGAUAAUAAAAAUAACCACUUUGAA